AGAGCCCGACUUCAGCCCCAGCCAGAUCCCGCGUCAACGGAGGCGGAACGGCGGACCCCGUACCCUGGCAGCAUCGGAGCACCGGCGGGUGAAGGCAAGGUCCCUGGACUGGUCAUAUACCUCUUGUGGCCCUGGCAGAAUCAAGAUGAGGCCCUGUCAUGCCUCCCCAGUGAGGCCUACAGUCUGAGCAGACAGCAUGGCCUGCCACUGGCAGUGAACACCAUGUCUGCAGGAGGUGGCCGGGCCUUUGCUUGGCAAGUGUUCCCCCCCAUGCCCACUUGCCGGGUCUAUGGCACAGUGGCACACCAAGAUGGGCACCUGCUGGUGUUGGGGGGUUGUGGCCGGGCUGGACUGCCCCUGGACACUGCUGAGACACUGGACAUGGCCUCGCACACAUGGCUGGCACUGGCACCCCUGCCCACUGCCCGGGCUGGUGCAGCUGCGGUAGUUCUGGGCAAGCAGGUGCUAGUGGUGGGUGGUGUGGAUGAGGUCCAGAGCCCGGUAGCUGCUGUAGAGGCCUUCCUGAUGGAUGAGGGCCGCUGGGAGCGUCGGGCCACCCUCCCUCAAGCAGCCAUGGGGGUUGCAACUGUGGAGAGAGGUGAGUGGCCUCCCAAGGAAGGCACUUCAGAUGGUAUGGUGUAUGCUCUGGGGGGAAUGGGCCCUGACACGGCCCCCCAGGCCCAGGUACGUGUGUAUGAGCCCCGUCGGGACUGCUGGCUUUCGCUACCCUCCAUGCCCACACCCUGCUAUGGGGCCUCCACCUUCCUGCACGGGAACAAGAUCUAUGUCCUGGGUACCCCAAUUCCAUUGACAGGGGGCCGCCAGGGCAAGCUCCCGGUGACUGCUUUUGAAGCCUUUGAUCUGGAGGCCCGUACAUGGACCCGGCAUCCAAGCCUACCCAGCCGUCGGGCCUUUGCUGGCUGCGCCAUGGCUGAAGGCAGCGUCUUUAGCCUGGGUGGCCUGCAGCAGCCUGGGCCCCACAACUUCUACUCUCGCCCACACUUUGUCAACACUGUGGAGAUGUUUGACCUGGAGCAUGGGUCCUGGACCAAAUUGCCCCGCAGCCUGCGCAUGAGGGAUAAGAGGGCAGACUUUGUGGUUGGGUCCCUUGGGGGCCACAUUGUGGCCAUUGGGGGCCUUGGAAACCAGCCAUGUCCUUUGGGCUCUGUGGAGAGCUUUAGCCUUGCACGGCGGCGCUGGGAGGCAUUGCCUGCCAUGCCCACUGCCCGCUGCUCCUGCUCUAGUCUGCAGGCUGGGCCCCGGCUGUUUGUUAUUGGGGGUGUGGCCCAGGGCCCCAGUCAAGCCGUGGAGGCACUGUGUCUGCGUGAUGGGGUCUGAAGGCUUGGUGGGAGCUGUCCACUGGAGCAGCUCAUUGCCAGAGGCAGCUAUUUCUAUGGCUCCUUUUGCUGCUGAGGACACUCACUGUGGCUCUGUGGGAUGAGAGAGGCAUGGGGGUGAGCACUUGAAACACUGCCUUGGGGCCUUGGGUUAGGGGAGCCUUUGUCUUUAGUGCAGGACACACAUAUGCUUACACCUACCUUUAUCACCAUUCGUUCAUGAAUCAUGCCUAGCUCCAUCCUUGCCCUGGGACCUACUAGGCCUUCCAUCCAACUGGGAAAUGGGGAGAAGCAAAGCUGGCCUCAUGCUCUUCAGGGUCAGUUCCUAUCUGGAGUUGACCAGGCCUACCCCAGUUGCCAUUCCUGAAAAAUCUCAGCUGCCAGGCUGCCUUUAGGGUCCCUGCAGACCCAGGAGAGUUGAGAGGGUGGGGGACACAGAGAGAAUAGAGAGGAUGUGGGAACUGCCAGAGGGCCGGAGCGCAGGAGUUCAAGUGGAGGAAUGCUGGCUUUGAGCCCUCUACACUGCUGGUUGUAUGACCUUGGACAAGUCACUUCACCUCUCUGUGCCUCAGCAUCCUCAUCUAUAAAUGGGGAUCUCUGAAACCUUCCUACCCUACCUACCUCACAGGGCUGUUGUGAGGACCCAGGGAGUUUGGAUGUGGAAGUAAAAGUGCUGCUAAAACCUA